ACUUCCGUCCAGACCGGAACCCAAGAUGGCUGCGCUGUUGCUGAGGUGACUUCAGUGGGACUGGGAGUUGGUGCCUGCGGCCCUCCGGAGAUCUGAACUGGCCCCUCACGUUUUGCUGAUAACUGUUUAUCCUGUGCCUGGGCAGGGAAAGGACCCAUGGGUGUGGAGGCCAAGCGCUCGGGGAUCCUAGAGACCCCUUUUCCCGUCCCCCCCAGCCGCUCCGGUGCGCUCCGUAGGGCUUCGGGGUCACUGACUUCGUAUCGAGGGGCCCUCGGCUCUCGCCCCUUCUGUUUUCCCCACCUCCUCUAGUACUUCUAACGCAAAUUGCUCUCGGGCCUGCACCCAGAGCCGAGCUCUGAGAAAAUAACUUCAAGGUCAGCCACCCAUGGGUCCUACGAUUUCGAGAGCGUAUUUAGACAUUUAGCUUCGGAGAGAGAGAUCUUCGUGUAUUUUGCCUUUGCUUCGAAUGCCUUCAGACACUAGCUGCUCCCACCACACGUUGGUCGUCAUUGCCUCCGAGCCCACUUUAGCCCUCAGCUCUGUAUCAGAAAUGCUGUUCCUUUGGGAACCACGGCCAAAGAAGAGAUGGAGCGGUUCUGGAAUAAGAAUAUAGGUUCAAACCGUCCUCUGUCUCCCCACAUUACUAUCUACAGUUGGUCUCUUCCCAUGGCGAUGUCCAUCUGCCACCGUGGCACUGGUAUUGCUUUGAGUGCAGGGGUCUCUCUUUUUGGCAUGUCGGCCCUGUUACUCCCUGGGAACUUUGAGUCUUAUUUGGAACUUGUGAAGUCCCUGUGUCUGGGGCCAGCACUGAUCCACACAGCUAAGUUUGCACUUGUCUUCCCUCUCAUGUAUCAUACCUGGAAUGGGAUCCGACACUUGAUGUGGGACCUAGGAAAAGGCCUGAAGAUUCCCCAGCUAUACCAGUCUGGAGUGGUUGUCCUGGUUCUUACUGUGUUGUCCUCUAUGGGGCUGGCAGCCAUGUGAAGAAAGGAGGCUCCCAGCAUCAUCUUCCUACACAUUAUUACAUUCACCCAUCUUUCUGUUUGUCAUUCUUAUCUCCAGCCUGGGAAAAGUUCUCCUUAUUUGUUUAGAUCCUUUUGUAUUUUCAGAUCUCCUUGGAGCAGUAGAGUACCUGGUAGACCAUAAUAGUGGAAAAGGGUCUAGUUUUCCCCUUGUUUCUAAAGAUGAGGUGGCUGCAAAAACUCCCCUUUUUUGCCCACAGCUUGCCUACUCUCGGCCUAGAAGCAGUUAUUCUCUCUCCAUAUUGGGCUUUGAUUUGUGCUGAGGGUCAGCUUUUGGCUCCUUCUUCCUGAGACAGUGGAAACAAUGCCAGCUCUGUGGCUUCUGCCCUGGGGAUGGGCCGGGUUGGGGGGUGGGUUGGUGAGGCUUUGGGUGCCACUGCCUGUGGGUUGCUGGCUUAAAGGACAAUUCUCUUCAUUGGUGAGAGCCCAGGCCAUUAACACCUACACAGUGUUAUUGAAAGAAGAGAGGUGGGGGUGGAGGGGAAUUAGUCUGUCCCAGCUAGAGGGAGAUAAAGAGGGCUAGUUAGUUCUUGGAGCAGCUGCUUUUGAGGAGAAAAUAUAUAGCUUUGGACACGAGGAAGAUCUAGAAAAUUAUCAUUGAACAUAUUAAUGGUUAUUUCUUUUUCUUGGAUUUCCAGAAAAGCCUCUUAAUUUUAUGCUUUCUCAUCGAAGUAAUGUACCCUUUUUUUCUGAAACUGAAUUAAAUACUCAUUUUAUCUUUGACUCUCCUUGAAA